AGCAGCUAGUCACGCUCGGUACCAGGCGCAGAUCAUGGCAGGCAGCCGGCUGGAAACCGUAGGGAGCAUCUUCUCUCGGACUCGGGACCUGGUUCGGGCCGGGGUGCUGAAGGAGAAGCCCCUGUGGUUUGACGUAUAUGACGCCUUUCCCCCGCUGAGGGAGCCCGUCUUCCAAAGGCCUCGAGUGCGAUAUGGCAAAGCCAAAGCUCCCAUCCAAGACAUCUGGUACCACGAGGAUCGGAUUAGAGCGAAGUUUUAUUCAGUGUAUGGGUCUGGUCAAAGAGCUUUUGAUCUAUUCAAUCCAAACUUCAAGUCUACCUGUCAACGGUUUGUGGAGAAGUACACUGAGCUACAGAAACUUGGAGAAACAGAUGAAGAGAAGUUAUUUGUGGAAACAGGGAAGGCUUUAUUGGCAGAAGGUGUCAUUUUAAGACGAGUAGGCGAAGCAAGGACUCAACACGGAGGUAGUCACGUUUCCCGGAAAUCCGAACACUUGAGUGUCAGACCACAGACUGCGUUGGAAGAAAACGAGACUCAGAAAGAAGUUCCACAGGACCAGCAUUUGGAGGCACCUGCAGACCAGUCGAAAGGUCUCUUGCCUCCCUGAAGGACCUGUAUACUGUGUAUGCUGGCAUUCACACUCUACUCACUGGCUGAAUGUUGAGCUAUUUUUAAACAGUUGAACUGUGUAAAUGUUUCUUGAUCUCUAAGGUAUUAUGUUUGCCUUCUCUUAGUUAUUUCUGGGUUGUCACAAAGCUCAGUAUCAUGGUUUGACAGAAGCAGUUAUGUGAACUUUUAUGUUAGGACAUUACUAAAUAAAGAAUUCCCUAGCUGCUUAUAAAGUAAAUUUACUUUGAAUUGUAAAUAACAUGAAGAAACCUUUAUAAAGAUUGUUCAAAUGGGACUCAAUCUGACUAGGCUUGCUUUGAUGUUUGUUAGUAUGUGGGCUGGCUACAUCUGAUUCCCGGGUACAUAUUUCUUCUGAUCCAUCAGACUUAUACGUGUACACAUGUUGUGGAACCUUGGCUAGCUGGUUUUGUCUGCAGAGAAUCUUUGUACUUCUUGCUAUAGAACGAUUAUCUCUCCACUUGAGAGGCCAAGCUGACUUGCGCUUUGUGGUAAGAGUGAGGACCUGUCAUUGCUGAUACACAAAGACCAAAACUGUAACUUUAAUGUCAUGGAUUGAGUGUGCUGGAGACAGUUAACAUAGGCCUGCACAGACUAGGCUGUUCAGUAAAUACUUGUUGAAUGAAUGAGUGAACGAAUGGUUAUAUCCAGCUAAAGACUGGAUUCAUAUGGUGUAGAUAACAGGAUUGCCAAGAAAGGAGGCAGCUAAUUUAGGUGAUGCUCUCCACCAGCAUCCACCUGCCUCCCUGGGGCCAAAGUGUGCCUACAAGUCCUUAUCAACUUCCCUGCCUUCCUCGUUUCCCCAGGUUUUACUAAAUACAUGAAAUAUCCCUCUGAGAUUGCAGCCUUUGUAUAUGUGGUCAAGCCAGUGGUUUUUAGCUGUUAGUAGUAAGCUGCUUCAGAAAUUCCCUAUUUUAAAACUCAUGUAGAUUUUCUACCCAGUGAUUCUUUGUGUAUGCUCUCAUCUCUCCUGGUACACUGUGAGGCAGGUCCACAUCUCACAGUCUGUAUAUAGUACACAUCCAUGCACGUGGGUGCUUGGUUCAUGCAGGUGAAUGAAUACAUUAGGCAAAAGCAGCUCUCAGCCAUGCUGCUUCCCCCUCGACCUUUAUCACUGUUUCACAACUGCUUGCAUUUGGAGAAUGCUUUACUUUUCCGUAGGGAAGUAAAUUUCAUCCAUUCAGAGACAUUACACAACCAUUGAGACCAAACAUCGGGCCAGACCUUGGGAAGAGGACUUAAAAAGCAGGUGAAAGACACAGUCUAUUCUCAGAGGAACAAUUGAGGGGUCACUCAUCUCUUUAAACCUUAGGUUUCUGGUUUUUUAAGGGCAGGUUUUUUUUGCCACAAUGAUGAAUAUUUAAAAAAUGUUUUUUUCCUUCAUGUCUGGAUUGAUGUCCCAUUUUUGCUAUUUUUGUUUGUUUUCCUCCUCUGUAGAUUUUUAAUUUUUUUUUUUUUUUUUUUUUUUUUUUUGCGAUGGAGUAUCACUUUGUUUCCCAGGCUGGAGUACAGUGGAGCCAUCUUGGCCCACUGCAACCUCCGCCUCCCAGGUUCAAGCAGUUCUUCUGCCUCAGCCUCCCAAGUAGCUGGGAUUACAGGUGUAUGCUAUGACGCCCGGCUAAUUUUUGUAUUUUUAGUAGAAACGGGCUUUUAACCAUGUUGCCCAGGCUGAUCUCAAACUGCUGGCCUCAAGUGAUCCACCCAUCUCAACCUCCCAAAAUGCUGGGAUUACGGGUGUUAGCCACCAUGCCUGGCCUUAAUUUUUUUUUUUUUUAAUUUUGUUUUAGGAGAUGGGGGUCUCACUGUGUUACCCAGGCUGGGUGCAGUGGUGCAUACCCUGCCGCAGUCUUAACUCCUGGGCUGAAGCCAUCCUGGCUCACUUCCCGAAUAGCUAGGACUAUAGGCAUGUGCCACCACGCCUGGCUCUUUAACAUUUUUUUUGUUUGUUUUUUUUUGUAGAGAUGGAGUCUUGCUAUGUUGCCCAGGCUGGCCUGGUCUCAAACUCCUGGCCUCAAGCGAUCCUCCUGCCUCAGCCGCCCAAAGUGCUGGGAUUACAGGCCUGAGCGACCGUACUGGGGCUGAAGACUUUUAAAGAAGUUAUUUGUUGCAUAAUUCUUUAAAAAAAUUAUACAUGCACAUGGUUCAAAACUUAACAGUAAAAAGCUAGUCUCCCACCCCUGUUCCCCAGCCACCCUUUUCCCCUUCCCUGAGGCCAUCACUAUCACCAUUUCCUUGUGCGCUCUUCCAGAAAUAUUUUGGGCAUGGACAGGACACUAUGCAUACUGUUCUGUACCUUGCUUUUCUAGUUACUAUGUCUCAGAGAUCCACUGUGAUUUAAUCAGUGCCCGAUUGAAGAAAAUGUUCUUUGUUUUACUGUGUUGCAAAUGGGCUGCUAGAGUUAUGGGAUGCUGGAUCAAGGAGCAGAUCAUUUUGAGUUUUGAUAUCUUCGUCCAUAGAAAUUGUGCUUAACUAUACUCUCAUAGCAAUGUAUGAGAAUGCGUUCCCCUACACAUUCUGAUCUUGUUAAACCAGACUGGGACUCUGGACCAGAAGGGAAAGACCAUCCCUGUAUAGCAAAUAUCUGGAUGGGGAGAAAGCUGCUGUCACUCAUUGACUUCUUUAGGUUAAGUCUUAGUGAUCAAAACAUAGUGAAAGAUAUGAAGCUUACUUUGGAAACUCAGAACUAUUUCCACAGUUUGGGCAAAAGCUGUCAUCAGAUCCCCAUCACGUUUUGGAGAGAAUGGAAGCAUGACCGCAUUCUUGGCUUUAAAGAGCUUAAAAUCAGGCCGGGCUCCAUGGCUCACGCCUGUAAUCCCAGCACUUUGGGAGGCCAAGGUGGGCGGAUCACCUGAGGUCAGGAGUUCGAGACCAGCCUGGCCAACAUAGUGAAACCCCAUCUUUACUAAAAAUACAAAAAAAUUAGCUGGGCGUGCGGGCGUGUGCCUGUAAUACCAGCUACCCGGGAGGCUGAGGCAGGAGAAUCGCUGGAACCCAGGAGGCAGAGGCUGCAGUUGAGCCGAGAUUGUGCCACUGCACUCCAGCUUGGGCGACAGAGCAAGACCCUGUCUCAAAAAAAAAAAAAAAAAAAUCUUAAAAUCGAGUUGGGACUACAAGAGUGACUUGUGAAACAGCAAGAUGAACAGGAAUCCUUUUAAACUUUGAUAUAAAAGUACAGUAGAGGUUCAGGGGCAAGGAAUCAGUUCUGGAUUUGUCUAGGAAUACUGCAUGAGAGCCUGGAAAGGCAGUGGGAUGGACAUGUACAUGCGGUUUCUUUGGGCAGGAACACCCUCCCUUCUACCAUGGUCUGUAGGAAUUGAACCUUCCGUGCCGUUUUCAAAUGCUGUCUGUGCUCGGAAAAUACAUAAUAUCAAGUCCCUUACUGAACCCCCUACAGAUUGUGUUCAUAAGGUGCUUCACUGCUGUUGGUCUACCUGGCCUACUGUUUGUACUCCUGCCUCAUUUACUGUGGCCUUCAUUCAAGUAGUAAUGAUUAUUUACCUAUUAAGAGUAUAGGGUGGGCGUGGUGGCUCAUGUAAUCCCAGCACUUUGGGAAGUCAAGAUGGGUAGAUCACUUGAAGUCAGGAGUUUGAGACCAGCCUGGGCAACAUGAUGAAACCCCAUCUCUACUAAAAAUACAAAAGUUAGCUGGAUGUGGUGGCAGCCUCCUGUAAUCCCAACUACUCGGCAGGCUGAGGCAGGAGAAUCGCUUGAACCCAGGAGGUGGAGGUUACAGUGAGCUGAGAUCAUGCUACAGCACCCCAGCCUGGGCGACAGAAGAGAGACACUGUCUCAAAAAAAAAAAAAAAAAAAGUAUAAAGGAGGGCAGAAAUUCUUAUUCUUUUAACCCAUUGAAACAUUAAACAGCCUUUCAGGAGCAGACCCUCCUACGGAUUUGCUGAAUCCAAGGCGAGGAAGGCAUAUAUCCAGGUUACAGUGAAGUUUGCCCCAGACAAGUAAUGAAGAUUUGGGUUCUAGAUCUGGAUACUCCAGGCAGUUUUUACUAUGUGACCCUGUGCCUGUCACAGUAUUUCAGCCUGUAAAAUAUGGACAAUGUUUGCCUUUUUGGCUUCCAGUUAGCUUUGUGAGGAUUAAUUGAGAUGAGUGCAAAGCUCAUUUGUAAUGUGUGGCUGGUGGUUUUAUUACUAUUUUGAGCAGUAGUGGAAAAGCCCAUUUGAACUGGUAGGAUGAGAUAAGAUCAUGGUGGCCUUGACAACUACAUGGAGGAGCCAGUUGGGUAUGGGAAAGUUUGAGCAGGGAAAGAAAGAAUGUAGUGAAAGCAGUGUCAGGUCAAAGAAAGGUUUGCCUAGGAGUGAUGUAAAGAAUGGGAUGGAGGAGUGGGCAGGGAAGGAGGAAAGAGGAGACAUGUCAGAGGGACCAAAAAGGAGGCAGCAAGUCCAAGGUCACAAACCUGAGUGACUAGAAAACUUAGCAGCAUCACUAACACCCAGUUGGUGACGUGGAACUGGUGCUCUCCUGGGAGAGAGCUUCAAUUCUCAACCUACUAAGUUGAAGGUGAUGGUGCUAUAUCUAAGUGGCAGACAGAGAUAAGGGAUAGGUGUCUACAGGGGCAAGAUUUGGAGCCAGGAGAAGAAAUGAGCUCUCCAAGGGUAGUGGGGAGAGAUCUGGGAUGUUGGGGGCUGGCAGGUAAAUGCUUUAAGUGAUAGAAUAGGAGGAAUGAGAAAGCCAGCAAAAGAAAUUCACGUCCCAUGUCUUCCAUCAUCUAUAUGUCUGACUUGUUUAAGUGGUCCUGGAUUCACCAAAUUUUAUAGAGCUCUGCCUCUGCCUUUAUUGGGUAGGCCUGAUUUUUGAUGAUGUCCUUAAAAGGCUAGCCUGAUUCUUCUUGUAGUUUUGUAGAACACUUUGUAUCGAGAGUUCUCUGAUAAUGAAAGUGGUAUUACAGAAUAAUCUGCCCCCGAAGGACUCCUGAUUUUGUUAAAGUGAUACCUUUCUCUGUAAAUAAAUGAUGGCGUGCCACUUAAAAA